AGACCCGGAAGUGGAUGGCGUGGAGAUAUGGCGCAACUGCGGCGCGGACACUUGACAUUCAGGGACGUGGCCAUAGAAUUCUCUCAGGAGGAGUGGAAAUGCCUGGACCCUGUGCAGAAGGCUUUAUACAGGGAUGUGAUGUUGGAGAACUACAGGAACCUGGUCUCCCUGGGAAUCUGUCUUCCUGACCUGAGUAUUAUCUCCAUGAUGAAGCAAAGGACAGAGCCCUGGACUGUGGAGAAUGAAAUGAAAGUAGCAAAAAAUCCAGAUAGGUGGGAAGGUAUCAAAGAUAUCAACACAGGGAGGAGCUGUGCAGUGAGAAGCAAAGCAGGAAACAAGCCUAUUACAAAUCAACUUGGAUUAACCUUUCAGUUACCUCUGCCAGAACUGGAGAUAUUUCAAGGUGAAGGGAAGAUUUAUGAAUGUAAUCAAGUUCAAAAGUUCAUCAGCCACAGUUCUUCAGUUUCGCCACUUCAAAGAAUUUACUCUGGGGUCAAAACCCACAUAUUUAAUAAACAUAGGAAUGAUUUUGUUGAUUUUCCAUUGCUGUCACAAGAACAGAAAGCACACAUUAGGAGAAAACCUUACGAAUGUAAUGAGCAGGGCAAAGUCUUCAGAGUGUCUUCAAGCCUUCCUAAUCAUCAAGUAAUCCACACUGCAGAUAAACCUAACAGAUGUCAUGAAUGUGGUAAAACCGUCAGGGACAAGUCAGGCCUCGCAGAACAUUGGAGAAUUCGUACAGGAGAGAAACCUUACAAAUGUAAAGAGUGUGGCAAGCUCUUCAAUCGAAUUGCAUACCUUGCACGACACGAGAAAGUGCAUACUGGAGAGAGUCCUUACAAAUGUAAUGAGUGUGGCAAGGUCUUCAGUCGAAUUACAUACCUUGUACGACAUCAGAAAAUUCAUACUAGAGAGAAACCUCAUAAAUGUAACAAAUGUGGCAAGGUUUAUAGUAGCAGUUCAUACCUAGCACAACAUUGGAGAAUUCAUACAGGAGAGAAACUUUACAAAUGUAAUAAAUGUGGCAAAGAAUUUAGUGGGCAUUCAAGCCUCACCACCCAUCUGUUAAUCCACACUGGAGAGAAACCUUACAAAUGUAAAGAAUGUGACAAAGCUUUUAGGCACAAGUUCUCCCUGACAGUUCAUCAGAGAAAUCAUAAUGGAGAGAAACCUUAUAAAUGUCAUGAAUGUGGCAAAGUCUUCACUCAAGUUUCACAUCUUGCACGACAUCAGAAAAUUCACACUGGAGAGAAACCUUACAAAUGUAAUGAGUGUGGCAAAGUCUUCACUCAGAAUUCACACCUUGCAAAUCAUCAGAGAAUCCACACUGGAGAGAAACCUUACAAAUGCCAUGUGUGUGGUAAGGUCUUUAGGCACAGUUCAUGGUUUGUACAGCAUCAGAGAAGUGUUCAUGAGAGAGUCCUUACAAACUGAGUUUGGCAAACUCUAUCAUAAGUUCUAGCAGUAAUCAACAUCCGAGAGUCUAUACUAGAAAGAAAUCAUUUAAAUGUACUAUAUGUGGCACAGGCUGUAUCGAGACCUACCAAAUCACUAGACAUCGAAACAUUCAUCUUUGGUGAAACCACACAAAUGGAUUGUGUGUGCCAAGGCCAACAAGUCAAAAUAUGUUGAACCUAAUGAUAUGAUGUGUAUAAAGGGUGCAAGGACACGUGGAAAUGAUCUGUAAUAUUCGGGUUAUUAAAAAUGUAAUUGGCUGGGCGCAGUGGCUCACACCUGUAAUCCUAGCACUUUGGGAGGUUGAGGCAGGUGGAUCACAAGGUCAGGAGUUUGAGACCAGCCUGGCCAAUAUGGUGAAACACCAUAUCUACUAUAAAUACAAAAAAAUUAGCCAGGCGUGGUGGCACAUGCCUGCAAUCCCAGCUACUCGGGAGGCUGAGGCAGGAGAAUUGCUUGAAUCCAGGAGGCAGAGGUUGUUGCAGUGAGCUGAGAUCGCGCCACUGCACUCCAACCUGGGUGACAGAGCGAGACUCCGUCUCAAAAAAAAAAAAAAAUUAUUUGGGUUUGAAAGGCCAGGGGCAGUGGUUCAUGCCUAUAAUCUCAGCACAAUAGAAAGCCAAGACAGGAGGGUCACUUGAUGCCUGGAGAUCAAGAUAAGUAUGGGCAACGUAGCAAGGCCCAUCCCUACAAAAUAAAAAAAAUAAGCCAGGCCCUUGGCAUGUGUCUGUAGUUCCAGCUACUCAAGAGGCCGAGGCAAGAGGAUUGCUCAAGCCCAGGAGUUUGAGAGUUUGAGCAGUGAGCUCUGAUCUUGCCAUUUGUACUCCAGCUUGGGUGACAGAGCGAGACCCUGUCUCAAAAGAAAAAAAAGGCUAGUUUUUAUGACUUCAACCUGAACUUUGAAAUUUCUUCAUGUGCCUUCCCUACAGGCCUUUCACUGUGGUCUGGGAAAGAAUCAGUAAGAUGACAGGGCUGACUUCAUUAGAUGAGGAGCGUUUCUAUCCAGUUUCCUGGAGGAAUAAGGACACUGCCUUUUCAGAUUAAAGAUUGUCUGAUUUAGAGACCAUGGAGGUGGACAGAGAAUAACAAAACCGUGAUGGCAGUCAUCAUGCUUAUUGCAGUUAGCACACACUUUUCCUGACAGGCACAGUGCUGCUGUGCUCUACAAAUGACCAUGAAAUAGAGCACGCCAUGACUUUAGGACACAGGGAUUUUUAUGGGAAGAGAGUUCAUCAGGGACUGAUUACGUAGGAGAGACGAUGCAGGGGAAAUGGUGGCCACCGUCUCCAUUGAAUAGCAAUAGCUGCUGUUUAGCAAAGACUGAUUAAAAAGUACUCUGAUUUUUCAAAUGGAAGAGAGAACAGUUAAAUCAGAGUAGAGAGUUUAAUCAAAACUACCAGUGGAACAUGUUCUUGAGUAGGAUUCACAUUUAACUGCUGGCAUAAUUUGCAACUGUUGGAUUUUCUCAUGUUUGGAACAAUAAAGUUGAAAUUUUCCAAAGUGUGAAUGAUUUACCUUCUUUCUACCAAUAUUGUUUUAUCUCGUCUCAGGAGGAUACUUUAUAGCAGACAAUAAUAAGGCACCAUUAGGAUUUUUAAAUUAAUUUAUUUUUAAAAUUAAAGUUCUAGUGUACAUGUCCACAACAUGCAGGUUUGUUACAUAGGUAUACAUGUGCCAUAUUCGUUUGCUGCACCCAUCAACUUGUCAUUUACGUUAGAUAUUUCUCCUAAUGUUAUCCCUCUGCCAGCCCCCCACCCCCCGACAGGCCCCGGUGUGUGAUGUUACCCGCCUUGUGUCCAGGUGUUCUCAUUGAUCAAUUCCCACCUAUGAGUGAGAACAUGGGGUGUUUGGUCUUCUGUCACUGUGAUAGUUUGCUGAGAAUGAUGGUUUCCAGCUUCAUCAAUGUCCCUGCAAAGGACAUGAACUCAUCCUUUUUAUGGCUGCAUAGUAUUCCUUUUUUUUUUUUUUUUUUGAGAUGAAGUUUUGCUCUGUCACUCAGGCUGAAGUGCAAUGGCACGAUCUUGGCUCACUGCAUCCUCUGCCUCCCGGGUUCAAGUGAUUCUCCUGUCUACACCUCCCAAGUAGCUGGAUUACAGGCAUGCACCACCAUACCCGGCUAAUUUUUUUGUAUUUUUAGUAGAGAUGGGGUUUCACCAUGUUGGCCAGGCCGGUCUCGAAGUCCUGACCUCGGGUGAUCCAGCCACCUCGGGUUCCCGAAGUGCUAAGAUUACAGGCAUGAGCCACGGCGCCUGGCCAGGAUUUUUAAGGUUGAAGCAUCCACAACAAUUUUGUGUGUGAAAUGAAAUGACAUGCACUUUUGGGUAUAUACACUUGGGUAAGUAUGAUUUUGGGUAAUAAUACUUAGUACUUAAGUUAUUCUCUCUACUCUUUGUUUUUGUUUUUUGUUUGUUUUGUUUUGUUUUGAGAUGGAGUUUCGCUCUUGUUUCCCAGGCUGGAGUGCAAUGGUGUGAUCUCGGCUCACCGCAACCUCCGCCUUCCAGGUUCAAGUGAUUCUCCUGCCUCAGCCUCCCGAGUAGCUGGGAUUACAUGCAUGUGCCACCAUGCCCAGCUAAUUUUGUUUUUUUAGUAGAGACAGGGUUUCUCCAUAUUGGUGAGGCUGGUCUCGAACUCCUGACCUCAGGUGAUCUGCCCACCUCGGCCUCCCAAAGUGCUGGGAUUAUAGGCAUGAGCCACCACACUUGGCCUACCUCUCUACUCUGCCCUAAGAUGCUUUUGUGGGUAAAGUGAAAAUCACAUAACAGUGCAGCUUCAUCAUCAUAUGCCCUCAAUGUUCAUCACUGUUGAUAAACAUGCACUGUAUUAUGUUUCUGUGUGCCUUUUUCUUGUGUGCCAAGUAAGACCCAUGGCAGGCACCUUCAUUUUCAGGAAGCGAAAAUACAGAUACAGUAAUAUGGAAAAUAGGACAAAGUGUGGACUUCAGGAUGAAAAUAUUGUAACAAUCUUGCUGUUGACCUCGUAGCGCUCAGUGACAUAAUUUGAAAAAAUAUUAAUGUUCAGAAAUGUUCUCUUGAGGAUGAACACACAGAUUGGGAAUUUCGUUUUGCUUUGGUAGAUUAACUAGAAACUUCACAUUUUCACCCUUAUAACCUUUUUGGUAAUUUGAACUUUUGAUCAUUCUUCUGGAACUGCUUUGACAUCCACCUGAAGUUUGGUUUGGGUAUUGAGAAUGAUGAUGCCAUUCACUAAUGUGAUCUCAAAAUGUUUACUCCAUAAUGAGGCUUUCUGGGGAGAGCAGGGUAGACUUCCCCGGUUGGUCCAAAUAUGACUAGGGAAUCGGCAUAGGUGACUGGCUUGGGGUAUGAUGAUUGUUAAGGGAUAGGGCUUGGGCAGGGGUGCCCACUUGUGGUUUGAACUUUCAGCUGGUGCCAAAGGAGUGGGCACUGAGGAUUUUUCAGUUGACCAGAUGGGCAGAAUAGGAAGAGGGAGUGCAGAGGUGUAAAAGGCGUUGGUGUUCAGACAUCACAAAAUGCAGUCAACUCUAGGACAACUCUAGCUUCCUCUGGAAGCUCCUGCCAUCUUGGUUAGGAAAGACUCUGAUUUUCUUCAUGAUAAUAUCUUACGUUCCUUUUAUAGUUACAGAUACAGGUCUCAUUGCACAAUAUGAUUGUUGAAAACACUUGUGAAAUUUUUUUAGUAAAAUUGCCUAAGAUACUUUUUAUAGUAGACAAUGAAAAUUAGUGUGUGGGUUUAUAAUAAAUAUAAUGUAUUAUAUAAUAUGAUUAAAAUAUAUUUGUUAUAAAUAUGAUAUUACUAGAAGAGCAUUUUUCCAAAAGCUAUGGAAAUGUCAUUUUCCCGUUACAGCAUCAAGCAAUAUAUUCCAUGGUUCAUUUUCAACUCUAAUAAAAUUAUAUUUUGUGUUUAUAUAUGCACGUAUAGACACAUAUAUAAUAUUUUUUUUUUACUUUUUUCUUUUUCUGUACAUUGCAUCCAGAUGCUAUGCUUGUUUGUUUUUUUUUUUGAGACAGAGUCUUGCUCUGUCACCCAGGCUGGAGUGCAGCGGUGUGAUCUUGGCUCAUUGCAGCCUCCGCCUCCCAGGCUCAAGUGAUUCUCCUGCCUCGGCCUCCCGAAUAGCUGGGAUUACAGACAUGCACCAUCACCACACCUGGCUAAUUUUUGUAUUUGUAAUAGAGAUGGGGUUUCACCAUGUUGGCCAGGCAUGGUCUUGAACUCCUGACUUCAGGUGAUCCACCCGCUUCGGCCUCCCAAAGUGUUGGGAUUACAGGCAUGAGCCACCAUGCCCGGCCAGAUGCUAUGCUUAAUACAUUUUUUCCGAAUGUCACUCUAGUGAAAAUUUUAGGGGACACAAAAAUGAGACUGUUGUUUGGAGACAAUAUUUUUUGACAAGAGUAUGCACAAGACAAUGGCAGGUAUAAACGUUUUAUUGUAAAUAUGAAAAAGGAAAAAAUGCUUUCACUAUAUUAGAGGACUUGAAGUAACGUGAAGUGAUUCCAACCCUUUAUCUUUAUUUUAUUUAUUUAUUUUAUUAUUUAUUUUUUUGAGAUGGAGUUUCACUCUUGUUGCCUAAGCUGGAGUGCAAUGGAGUGAUCUCAGCUCACUGCAACCUUCACCUCCCGGGAGCAUGCUGCUCUAUCUUUUUUUUCAGAUGUUUGAGCUAUUCCAGGUUUUUUGGGAUUUCUGUUGGUUUGUUUUGUUUUUUGCUUUUCUACAUAAUUGUUUGGAUAAUCUUGUCAGUAUCUACGAAGUGCCUUGAUAGUAAAUAUAUUAACCCUGUGUAUCAAUUUGGGGUAAUUUCACAUUUUUUUCUAUGUUGAGUUUAUCAAUAAAUUGAUAUUGUAUAUGUCUCUA